AGCGUGUGGAGCUGCCUGCGCUCCGCCCGGGCUGUCAGUCCCGGCUCCAGCCGCCGCGAGACCUUCCCGGAGACGCGCGCACACACAGCGCACCCCCUGCACACCGCACACCCUCGCUCCCUUGCUCACACACACGCACACACUCAGCCUGGCCGAGCAGGAGCCACUGACCAUUUUGCAAGUGUCAGGACCAGCUACAGCGCGGUGGGCGCAAACAUCCCGCUUUCCCUUUCCGGGAUUUAGUCUGGGAGACGACGACGAGGGAAGAAGGUGGGCUCGGACGCAGCCCAGGCGCCGGGCACUGGUCGGGCCGUUUUCCUGGCAGAGCCGCUCCCCGGGACGGGCGCGGGCCUCGGGUGAGAGUAGAAUAAAGAGGAGCGGCCGCAGCCGCCGCGCGAGGAGGAUGGGAACUCCCCUAUUUCCAGCUCUGGAAACAAAUGGAUGGAAGUCCUGAAUGGAGCAACUGCUGACUUCAUCUGCUUGGAAAAAUAGUCCAGAGGAACUCAUAUUUGGCUACUCAGAGCAGUGGAGGGGGUGUCCAUGACGUGGCAGGGGGAAAAUAGACAACUGAAACCUCCCGUGUGAACUGCAAACUGUGACCAAGCAAGGGGAAAAUGAUCUUUCUGUAUAUAUUUUAAUUUCGUGCAAAGGUUUUCAAGCAUCUGUAUCCUAAACUUACUUCUAUGUCUUGUUCAGCAGAAACCAGAGGAGUCCUGUCUGGGGGUCCCAUCAUUAUUCGGGAUACCCGCCGCCAGCGGCCUGCCUUCGGUUACCCACAUCCCCCUGGAACGGAUAUCUGUUUGGGGCACUACAAUCUAUCCUGUAGAACUAUGGCCAAAUCUCCAUCAAUGCUUUGCUAAUUUCUGGGACUUAACUCGUAGAAUCUACAUACAGGGCUGGAAUUUAUUCAAAAUGCAUCUGAAGAAAUGACAUUUUAAACCGUUUUAAAAAAUAUCUUGAUAAAAAAUUCUGUAAAACAGAAUUUGAUAGGUUUAAAAACAUGACAGGUAAGAACUUUCUCUUUCUAGUCCCUUAACACCCGUCGUGGGGAAGGUCAAAGCAGGACCCAGGAGGAAGGAGAGAUCCGGGACCCGUGUGCCCUUCGGGGCUCAAAGGCGCUGGGCGGGCGGCUGCUUUCGGGAGAGGCGCAGCCCUCACUCCUGGACCACGGGGCCAGUGGCUGGGGAAGCUUCUGGGGCGCGCGCGGGGAGGCGGCGCUGCGCUCCACCUGCCCAGCCCCGGACGCAGCCCGGGGGCGAGGCGUCUAGGGACCACCCCAAUUCAAUAUUGGGAUUUUUAAUAAACCAAGGAAUGGGAUUUUAAUUAUUGAAAACCCAGCUCCUCUGGGCCAGAAUGGUGUUGGGAUGGUCCUGGUCACAAAAUAUUAAAGAGACCGACCGCUAAGGGAACAGGAAAAACGUCCGAGACAGCCGUUGCAAUUACGAAUGGACCAGACUUGGUAGCACGGGGCAUUGAUUGCUGGUGCCCAACCGGACCCUCCUCCCCUCUUCCCAUCCCUUCCCCCACCCAAAGCAGGCUCCCGCUGCGGCCGGGACCUCGCAUCCCUGCAACGUGGCCGGGGCUGCAUUUUUCAUGAGCCUAGGGUGAACAGGUGCGAAGUGCGCUGGGAGCAUCCGGCCAGCGGCCGAGCGCGGGGAACAUGGAGAGCGAGCGCGACAUGUACCGCCAGUUCCAGGACUGGUGCCUCAGGACUUACGGGGACUCAGGCAAGACCAAGACGGUGACCCGUAAAAAAUACGAACGGAUCGUCCAGCUCCUCAAUGGCUCCGAGUCGAGCUCCACGGACAACGCCAAAUUUAAAUUCUGGGUCAAAUCGAAGGGCUUCCAGCUGGGCCAGCCGGACGAGGUCCGCGGGGGAGGCGGCGGCGCCAAGCAAGUGCUCUACGUGCCUGUCAAGACCACGGAUGGCGUAGGGGUAGAUGAGAAGCUAUCUUUACGACGGGUAGCUGUGGUUGAAGAUUUCUUUGACAUUAUUUAUUCGAUGCAUGUGGAAACGGGGCCAAAUGGAGAACAAAUUCGGAAACACGCUGGACAAAAGAGAACUUACAAAGCAAUACAGAAAAAUGUGUGAAAUGCUCAAAGUUUCAAAUACAGAUUUCAGAGAGCUAUGCCUUCCUACCAAGAGAAGCGGUGACACGAUUUCUAAUGAGCUGCUCAGAGUGCCAGAAAAGAAUGCAUUUAAACCCAGAUGGAACAGAUCAUAAAGAUAAUGGAAAACCUCCCACUUUGGUGACCAGCAUGAUUGACUACAACAUGCCAAUUACCAUGGCCUACAUGAAACACAUGAAGCUGCAGCUGCUAAACUCACAGCAAGAUGAGGAUGAAAGUUCAAUAGAAAGUGAUGAAUUUGACAUGAGUGAUUCAACACGGAUGUCAGCUGUGAACUCUGAUCUUAGCUCCAAUCUUGAAGAAAGAAUGCAAAGUCCCCAGAAUCUUCAUGGCCAGCAAGAUGGUCAACAGAAAAGACAUACAGAAGGCAGAGGCUGUGGAAAAGGAUUUGAGAAAAAACUAGAAAUUAUGAUUCUGCUGCAGAGAGCUUUAAUGGCAAUGAGACUCUGGGGCACAGUUCAAUUGCUUCAGGGGGAACACACAGCAGGGAGAUGGGAGACUCCAACAGUGAUGGCAAAACUGGGCUGGAGCAAGAUGAACAGCCACUGAACCUGAGUGACAGUCCCCUCUCUGCGCAGCUAACUUCGGAAUACAGAAUAGAUGAUCACAACAGUAAUGGGAAAAACAAGUAUAAGAAUCUUCUAAUUUCUGACCUCAAGAUGGAACGAGAGGCGAGAGAAAAUGGAAGCAAGUCUCCUGCACAUAGUUACUCCAGCUAUGACUCUGGCAAAAAUGAGAGUGUAGACCGAGGAGCUGAGGACCUCUCACUAAACAGGGGAGAUGAGGACGAAGAUGACCACGAGGACCAUGACGAUUCGGAGAAAGUUAAUGAGACAGACGGCGUUGAAGCCGAGCGGCUGAAAGCUUUUAAUAUGUUUGUCAGGCUGUUUGUAGAUGAAAACUUGGACCGAAUGGUCCCAAUCUCUAAGCAGCCCAAAGAAAAGAUCCAGGCUAUCAUUGACUCAUGCAGGCGACAAUUCCCUGAGUAUCAAGAGCGUGCCAGAAAACGUAUACGUACUUACCUCAAGUCCUGCAGGCGGAUGAAAAGAAGUGGUUUUGAGAUGUCUCGACCUAUUCCUUCCCACCUUACUUCAGCAGUUGCAGAGAGUAUCUUGGCUUCAGCUUGUGAGAGUGAGAGUAGAAAUGCCGCCAAGAGGAUGCGUCUGGAGAGACAGCAGGAUGAGUCUGCUCCAGCUGACAAACAGUGUAAACCAGAGGCGACCCAGGCCACUUACUCAACAUCAGCUGUUCCAGGCUCACAGGACGUGCUGUACAUCAAUGGAAAUGGGACCUAUAGUUACCAUAGUUACAGAGGGCUAGGAGGGGGUCUGCUAAAUCUGAAUGAUGCUUCCAGCAGUGGACCCACUGAUCUCAGCAUGAAGAGACAAUUGGCGACUAGCUCAGGAUCCUCCAGCAGCUCAAACUCCAGACCCCAGCUGAGUCCAACUGAAAUCAAUGCCGUGAGACAGCUUGUUGCAGGAUAUCGAGAAUCAGCUGCAUUUUUAUUGCGAUCUGCAGAUGAACUGGAAAAUCUCAUUUUACAACAGAACUGAGACAGACGACCACCAUAUUCACUGAGGUCUAAAUUUGCAGUUUCCACUAAUGACAUUUUGAUUUCCCAACAGAGAUACUUCUGGUCUUACUGCACAGUCUUUUAAGAGAAAUACUUCCAUUAUGCCACAUUGUCCUUGAUCCGUAAGUGAUGUGUUAAGGUGCUUCAAAGGAACUCUGACCUCUGAAGUACUUGAGCUACUUUAGUAUGUCCAGCCUAUUGCUUUUUGUUUUAGUGUGUCACCAUAAAUAUCAGGGGCAUAAAAGGCUAUCUAUUCUUAAUUCAAGGAUAAAACAGAAGAAGCUUGUGGUAUAAAACAAUAGUUCAAGAUCCAGCUGAAAUAUUAGUGGAAUUUGCUACUGACUCAUUGGACUGAAAGCUGAAGUACCUGGCAAAAAAAAAAAAAAGAAAAAAAAAAGCCAAAUUUCUUGUUGCUACAGGAUAUAACAACAAUGAAAAGGAUCUCGUAUUUUAAAAAAAUAUGUAAUUUUUAUAAAAAGAAAACUUGUUUUUCAUUCAAACUUGUCAUUUUUACUUUGGUAACUUUUUCAUAGGUCCUAAAAGAAAACUGUUUUGAGAAACUACUGUAAGUACCUUUUCCACAUCCCUUUGCCUUCUCCUCUUUCCAAAUUCUUUCUACAAAAAUAACACUUGAUGCUGGAAAAACCCUUGCCUACGUUCUUUCAAUCGUCACAUCAGGAACUACUUCCAAGAGAAGCCUGCAUUUCUGCUCUCAUGCUGAUCUCAAAAACCCCACUCAACACUGCAACUUUAUCAUAGCAGUUUUCAUCCCAGAAUUUUUUUUUUAAUAAUGACAAGACAUGUUGUUGAAAAAAAAUCACACCUUGGUUUCUUAGAGCUGCUCGUUCCUGAUUGCCGCUGCUGUCUCCAGGCAUCCCUCUAGCAGCACCUGGAUGUAGAUGACUGAAUGUUAAGAGGUUGCAAGUGACAAUCUGAAAAUUUGCACUCUUGUGUGUAGUUUUCUUUUCAUUUCUUUCAGAAAUAGUUUCCAAAAAGACCAUUACAUCUCCUGAUAUGAUUUGUAUAAUUUUCAGUUCUAGCUAAAAAUAAUGUAAGGAACUCUCAGCGGAUGCAGCUGCAACUUACAAUGAACUGUGCCCUCCUAUCCCCCAUACUUUACCCUUCUUUCUUAUUUUAUAGUGUGGGAUACACAUGAGUGAUGUUUUCUUUGUGCACUGAGACAAGCCUAUUUUUUAAAUAUUUAGGGAGAAGUACUUUAGUUCAUGCUUCUUAUACAACUUUUUUCUGUUGUUUAGCUUUGGUUGGAUUACAAAUUCUUUGUGCAUUCCUGAAUUUGCCUUAUUUCAUGUAAAAUUUAUGUCAUUCAGUUUUUGACAAUGAGUUUGAGGCAUCAGUGAUAUUUCUUAUCUACUUGUUACAUAUAGUUUUUCAAGUAAUGACUGUGAUUGUGACCGAGUAAUGUGCACUUUUUCUUGUAACUGUGGACAUUGCUAUGCUUUUUUCUUCUAGUGUUUCUAGAAUUACUGUUCCUUACAAUUAUGUAAACAAAAAACAAAAAAAAAACUUUUGUGAUACUGUUGGUGAAUAUAAUGUGAAAAAUCUUAUUGAAAUAUGAGUAUUUUGGAAAUACAUAGCUGCACAAACAUCUUUUAAGAUGUGGAUUUAGAGUUUGCUUAUUUAAAUGAAAAUUCAAAAAUUGAGGGCUGGUAUAAUUUUCUCUGUUUUGUUUGGUUUAAUAAACAGAUUUCUGUGUUAAAAGAA